AGUCCCGGGUGCCGCGGGGACAGUGUAGGGUCAUUAGCUGUUGAGCCGCCCCGGGCGGGCCCAAGCCUUUGGAUCUCAGGUGACCGGCACAGGCGGCCGCGGGGUCCGGAACUGCUUGUUCCGGCAGUGGAAGAGACGCGCCGGCGUUGGCCGCUGCUGCUAGCAGCUUGAACCCCAGGGUCGGGACCGAUGUCGGCUUGGGCUGCUGCCAGCCUAAGCAGGGCCGCUGCCCGAUGCUUGCUGGCACGAGGCCCCGGGGUCAGGGCGGCUCCUCCGCGCGACCCCCGGCCCUCCCACCCCGAGCCCCGGGGCUGCGGUGCCGCUCCGGGCAGGACGCUGCACUUUACCGCGGCUGUCCCCGCCGGGCACAACAAGUGGUCCAAAGUCAGGCACAUCAAGGGUCCGAAGGACGUCGAAAGGAGUCGCAUCUUCUCCAAACUCUGUUUGAACAUCCGCCUGGCAGUGAAAGAAGGAGGCCCCAACCCUGAGCACAACAGCAACCUGGCCAAUAUCUUAGAGGUGUGUCGCAGCAAACAUAUGCCCAAGUCAACGAUUGAGACAGCACUGAAAAUGGAGAAAUCCAAGGACACUUAUUUGCUGUAUGAGGGUCGAGGCCCUGGUGGCUCUUCUCUGCUCAUCGAGGCAUUAUCUAACAGUAGCCACAAGUGCCAAGCAGACAUUAGACAUAUCCUGAAUAAGAAUGGAGGAGUGAUGGCUGUAGGAGCUCGUCACUCUUUUGACAAAAAGGGGGUGAUUGUGGUUGAAGUGGAGGACAGAGAGAAGAAGGCUGUGAACCUAGAGCGUGCCCUGGAGAUGGCAAUCGAAGCAGGAGCUGAGGAUGUCAAGGAAACUGAAGAUGAAGAAGAAAGGAACGUUUUUAAAUUUAUUUGUGAUGCCUCUUCACUGCACCAAGUGAGGAAGAAGCUGGACUCCCUGGGCCUGUGUUCUGUGUCCUGUGCACUAGAGUUCAUCCCCAACUCAAAGGUGCAGCUGGCUGAGCCCGACCUGGAACAGGCCGCACAUCUCAUUCAGGCUCUCAGCAACCACGAGGAUGUGAUUCACGUCUAUGAUAACAUUGAAUAACCAGGCUACAUGUGCCCCCGGGUUCCUUCCUAGAAAUGUGGCAGCCCAUUCCAGCACACAGGCUUCUGCAGCAAUCUCUGAGGGUAAAGCCGGUGGGAGGCUCAGCAGGCCAGGAGGCCCAAGGACAGGACUUGCGACCUUGAAGCCAAAGGAAUCUCACUUGUGGGGCCUCCUUGUCAGCUCUGCUGCUGUCUCAGAGCCAUCUGGAUGAGUGUCCCGACACCCUCUCGGAUGCAGGGCAGGACCACCCAGCUGGUCAGACUCUGAUGUUGGGUAGCUGGCCUCUGUGGGGAUUGUAAGUGCCCUGAGGCGCUCUGUACUAGAAACUGCUCUUAAUAAUAACGGUGAUUAUUGGUUGCUGCA